UGGCCUAAAGGAAUAAUAUUAACGUAUAUGAAUAUCUAAUAUUCAUAGCUAUGUAUGCUAUAGCUUUACCAUUGGGGCAAGCCAGACCAUGAAAGAACUGUACCCCACAUUAUAUACAUUUGCUUUCUGCUUCACAUUUGGGUGUUAUGACAUCAGCUGCCCUCCCAGACCCACCGUUCUAGGGUACAGCAGAACUCAAAGUGUUUGUCAACUUGGACUUCCGCCUGUCCACUAGCUUGCCUUAAGCAGAUUCUGAGGAGCUGCACUCAAGAUUGAUCCCCUAUGUUCUUUUGGUCUCAUAUUCUCUAGCCUUUCUUGUAACAGGCAUACCAGGUCAAAUGAGGGACAUCUGUCCAUUUGCAAACAAGCCAACCUCAUCCCUGAGGUCAGUGAUGAAGUGCUGAGUAACGAACUGGAAAAGCAAAUAAGUAAAGGAGUUAGGAAGGACACUUUCUUAUUCGGAGCUCACUAGAGAAUGUGAUUUUUCCUGAACAACUGCAUACUUCCUAGUAUGCCUUUUGGUAAACUACCCACGUUUCCCACAAUAUGUACCUGAUAUGGAGAGGGAAAAAAGCAAACCAUGGCGGUCUAAGCAGCUUAGAUUUGAUAAAAAUAAUAAGAGUGGUUCCUUCAGUUCAUUUUCCAAACCCUUCUGCCAGAACAAGCUGGUUCUUCUGGGAAGACGGAACUGCCUACGGCCAUAUGCACCCAUCUGUUCUUCUCUGCAAAAAUGUCUUGGCCUUUUCCACACAGAGCCAGUGGGUGGUGGGGGUGACCACUGCAGGUGGACAGGCCAGAUUGCAAGAGCCCCCAUUCUAGAGAGGGUCCUGUCCCAUACCCAGAAGGAAGGAAUGCUGCACAGAGGCCAAGAAGAAUCCAGACAGACAGGCCUUGCCGGGCUUCCCCGCUCAGUCUGUUUGUUUUAGACCAUGCCUUCUUUGUCCAGUCAUAUUUCUACAAGCCUGACCAUACUUUGCUGAACCAAAGCAUGAACAUGGACAGUUUGCUCUAUAUCUUUGGGUCUUCAUCCUGAAGGAUCCUGUGUCACAUAUAAAACUAUGAUCAAAUAAAUUUGUAUGCCUUCCUCCUA